GUGGCCGUCGAGGUGGGGCUCGGCGGGUCCGAAGGAACCUGGGGCAGAGCUGGAAGAGGAAAGGUCUUGGGGGCCCUGGGCCUGGGUCUGCGGGAGCCCCAUCUAGCGGGGUUCCAAGGCGGCGGCGGCAUCAGUCGAGGCCCUGCUCCGGGAGCUCAUCUUGUCCCCUUUCGCCCCUCACGCCCCCCAGCUCUGACUCCAGGCCCUGUCCCCUGAGCUCUGCCCUCGGAUGUCCGACCGCCCAGAGCCUGCAUGCGCCGUGGGGCGCCCCAGGACCAGGAGCUGGUGGGUCCGGGGCCCCCUGGGCGGGGGUCCCGGGGCGCCCCUCCUCCCUUGGGACCCGUUGUCCCGGUCCUGGUCUUUCCCCCGGAUCUAGUAUUCAGGGCGGACCAGCGGAGCGGACCCCGACAGCUGCUGACCCUCUAUAACCCCACAGGAACUGCGCUUCGCUUCCGAGUCCUGUGCACAGCACCUGCCAAAUACACGGUGUUUGACGCAGAGGGAUAUGUGAAGCCCCAGUCUUGCAUUGACAUUGUGAUUCGCCAUGUGGCACCCAUUCCCAGCCACUAUGAUGUCCAGGACCGCUUCCGCAUUGAGCUGUCUGAGGAAGGAGCUGAGGGCCGAGUGGUGGGACGCAAGGACAUUACCUCCAUUCUGAGAGCCCCAGCGUACCCCCUUGAGCUUCAGGGACAGCCAGAUCCAGCGCCUCGCCCAGGGCCUCCUGCUGGGACACCACCACCCACGGCCAGACACUUCCAGGAGCACCCCCGCCAGCAACUGGCCACCAGCUCCUUCCUCCUCUUCUUGCUGACGGGGAUUGUGUCUGUGGCCUUCCUGCUGCUCCCACUCCCGGACGAACUCGGCAGCCAGCUGCCUCAAGUCCUGCACGUCUCCCUGGGACAAAAGUUGGUGGCCGCCUACGUCUUGGGCCUCCUCACCAUGGUGUUCCUCCGGACCUGAGCUCCGUGCUCAACCCCCAGCCCACCCCACCCUCCCUGGGCAGGGUCUUGAGGCAGCCACUGUGAUGCUCAUACCUUACCUUGCCUCCUACCCUCUUCUCUUUCCUGCCUACUCCCCACUCCUCCCUGACAAAAAACACCCAGGGAUUUGUACUCAUUUUCCAAGUUGAAUAAAAUACAUUUUUAAAAUGAUAA